CUUCACACAGGAAGUUUCCUUCUCUGUUGUCAGAUUUAGCACUGUGCUCUUGUCAUCAGAUCCGAGCCAGGCUCCCUGCUGCACAGUAGAGAGGCUUCCUUAAGACAUUUGUCCUUGAAACUGCACCAAACUCUUGGAAGAACCCAGAACGUGUAAGUAUGUAUGAUUUAGGCAGCAAUAGUACAGGGCAAAGCUGCAAUCAACCAUUAUACAAUAUCCGAUUAGCAGUGCAGGAGGGAUUUUUCCGACGUUAUGUUACAUUCAUUUUCAAUUUGUUCUGAGGAAACAAAUCAAUUCUAGCUUCUGAUACAGUGACUUUGCAGUAGAUGGGGUUGUAAUAUGUUAGCUUUAACUAUUUGCUGUUCUCAUUUAGCAUUUAGAUGUGACUUGUGGGACAAUUACUGUGGGCAUUAAACUAUAAAACUUCUAAAUUUUUAUUAGGAAUUGUAAUUGUUGGUCAUGUCCAUCUUGAGAAACAAGUUAGCUUUGGGGAAUGUUUUUAAAGAAUUAACCACAUAAAUUCAUGGACAAAAGAAUGAAUUUGUACUGUUCUUGCUCUCAAAACAUAUUAGUUUGCAGUUUUAAUUUACUCGUAAAGAGCAUUCCACUGAGGUUUUGUCUUAAUUGAAUCCUACCCAGUGCUGUCUGUUUGGUGUUUUACUGUCUUGUAUAUAUCUGUUUAAGUUACUUCGCUAGGAUUGCAGUCUGGUUAAACCUGUAUUUAGCCACUACCUAGAUUCUAAGAACAUUCAGGUCAGUAAAUGCUCACAGAAUUUUGGAAAGUGGUGGAUUUGUUUUCAAGGGUGGUCGUAUUACCCUUGAAAGCUUUUUAGGUGCACAAUGUGAAUGGCUGUCAGAUGGAGACCACAGACUGAACACUCUAAGGCUCUAAGUCAAAUCUCGGCUUGUCCACUUUCAUAACUCCAAUUAACUCCAACCAAUAAAAGCCCAUGCCCCCUUUCUAUCAAUUUUUAAUAUGCAACAAUACUUAUGUUUAUGAGAUUAAUUUCUCUCAGAUUAGUCUGAUUGAUAGCUGGAUUGUGGUUUCUUAAGAGCUUGCUCCCUGAAACCCACAGCAGAGCUGCAUUCCAUUUAACUAGUGAAUGUAAAAACGGGUAACCAUGGAUUCAGCCACCACUAACUGCCAGUGCAAUGACUUGUUGUAAACAAUACAAAUGAGCCAGGAGAGCAGAGGCAACCAGACAUGAAAUGAUUUUAAUAGAAAUUACGGUAAAAGGUCAUGUGAUUUGGUAUCAGCUUCUGUUCAGUUUUAAAGGGAAAGUCUUUAUUUUCUCCCCCUUCUUCCCCCCUUACCUAUUUCCAACCAACCCAAGUAGGUAUCUCCACAAACUUGGCAGGUCCCACUCUGUGCUUCCAUGGAGAAGGGCGGCCAAUGUGAUUCUGGGCAAAGUGUGGUGACUUGUGGAUUUUCACUGGUAAGUACCUUUAUUUUAGAAACAAAAAGGAAGUCUGUAUUUCAGGGCUUCCUUUAUGGAAGGUCAAGCUAAUUGCGUACUAGAAGUUCUCAAGUCUUGACAUAAGAGGAAUAGGUCAUUUCGUUCCUUAGCUUUUAAAUGGUACAACUGUCUUUUCUCUCUCUCUCCCUGUCUCCAGAUUAAUUCGUAAACUCAGUCUUUCUGAAAACUGUUAUUUGCUUUAGAAACAACUUCUGCCAUAUGGUAAUAAGCACAUGCAGAUACUGUGAGAAGUGCUGUGUCCUAACUUCAGAGUUUUCAUCUACCCAGAUAUUUUCUGAGUUCUACGAGGACCAGAUAUCACAAUAAUAUUUGCAUUUCUCUGGUAGAGGUGGUUUCAGUGUGUGAAAAUGAUUGUAUUCAUAAAUUUGCCUUCAACCGAGAAAAAUGAGCAAAUUGUACCUGUGUUAAGUGCUAACCUCGUGGUUUGUUUGGUGUGCUGUUAUCUGCUAUGCUUAUUUUAAAAACUAAGUGAGGAAUGUCUAGUAGCCAAAUCUGGGGGGAAAGGGGACAUUUGGAAGCAUAGCCGUGUCUUUAUCCAGAUUUGGAGGUGGAUCUAGUCAGUACACAGCAUGCAUGCAGGAAUGAAGAUGCUCAGAGUCACAGUCUCAAGGAACCACAGGCACUUUAAGCAAAGGACUCUGUCUAGGUGUGCUGAGCUUCAAGGUGAAACAGACCUGAACUGGUUUCUUGAGCCAUACUUCCUUCCACAUACAGAUGGUAUAAAUAAUUGCAUCAUCCUGGAACAAAAGAUAAUGGCUCUUUUAACUCCUUUUAACAUAUAGAUUCUUCUGAAUAGAUGCAUCAUUGUACAUAUACAGGUGUCAUACUGAAUGAUAGAAUUUCAGGUGUGUAUUUUUCUAUUAAUACCUCUACUGUAAUAGAACCAAUCAGCACAUGAAAAAGCAUGAGGGUUAUAAUUUAGAAGCUCAAUAAAAUGUAAAAGCAUCAACCCCCUCUACAUACACUCCAGAUUUUAUCUGGCAAACUCUUUGUUUAGAACUGUAAGUGCUAAGUGUUAACAUAGUGCUUAUAUUUAAGCUUUUUUUAAAAUCAAUCUUUUUAAGAUGUUGGAGAGCCUUAUUGCAUGCUUAGACUGAAAAAUGUUUCAGAAUAUCAUGGUUAAUACUGUGAUCUCAUGGUGUGUUUUCUAUUCUAAUACCAGCUAUGUUUAUCAAAAAGAUAUAAAAGAAUAGACUCUAGUAAUUAAUGUUGGGGGGGGGAAAGGAGCAAUUUGAAGCGAGUGUGGGAACACCAAGUAUAAGUGGAGUUUGGGGUAAAAUAUAAUAAAAAUAUGCUGUUUUUACUUUUCCUCACCUUGAUUCUCCAAGCUGAAAGAUAGGACUAAAAGUGUUAGGUACAGGGUGAUUAUGAAGCAUAAUAUUCAGAGUCAGACAUGGGUUGGGGUUUUGCUCUGGACCUAACCAUGUUUAAUAUUUUUAGGCCAAGUGACUUCACCUACCUGACCUUCCACAUUCUCAUCUGUAGAGUGAGGGUAAUAAUGUAUACCAAUGUUGGCUGAAAGAGUUACAUGAGAUAACAUAUGGAAAGUAUUCAGCAGUGUGUCUGGCAGAGUAAGUGUCCAGUAAACUGUUGCUGGUUUCAUUAUUAUCUUGACCCUCGAACAACAUGGGUUUGAACCAUGCAAGUCCACUUGUGGGUAGAUUUUUUUACAACCUAACACCGAUCAAAACUACAGUGUUUGUGGGCUGUGAAACCCAUGUCCAGAGGGCUGACUUUUCGUGUACGUGGGUUCAGCAGGGCUGAUUGCAGGACUUGAGUAUGUUUAGGCUUCGGUAUAUGCAGGAGUCCCAGAACCAAUCCCCAAGGAUACUGAGAGAUGACUGUAUUUUUGAUUGAGGAAAAAUAUCAUCAAGUAGAAUCCUGCUCUGUGUGCUUCACAGAGGAGGACACUAUUCACACCAUUGUUUGGUCCUGUCAUAGUGACAACUGUACAUCACAGUAGCUUUCAUCACUUGGGAGAUGGUGAUUCAUUUUGUAACAUAGUAUAGUGUUUUACUUUUAAAAAGUAUGUUUUUUGAGAUGGGGUCUUUCUCUGUUGCUCGGGCUGGAGUGCAGUGGCACAAUCAUAGCUUAUUGCUGCCUUAAACUCCUGGGCUCAAUUUUUUAAAUGUUUUGUAGACAUGGCGUCUUGCUUUGUUGCCCAGGUUGUUCUCGAGUUCCUAGGCUCAAGCUGUCCUCCCACCUUGGCCUCCCAAAGUGCUAGGAUUACAGGCAUGAGCCACUGCACCUACCCUAUAUAACACUGUUAUUAAAAACCAAAAGUAAUAUUUAUAUUCAUUAUUUUUUAAAUUUUCAUACAAAUUACUUAGAAAAACUAGUUGAGUUUUUUUUUUUUUGGGGGGGGUGGAUUUCUGAUACUGUGGGUAUUGAGGCUAAAUGCACAUUUUAUGUGUAAUUCUAUUGGUAGGGUCAAGGCAGAGGGACAUUUAAAGGGAUUCAUGGCUGGGCGCGGUGGUUCAUGCCUGUAAUCCCAGCACUCUGGGAGGCCAAAGUGGGUGGAUCAUCUGAGGUCAGGAGUUUGAGACUGGCCGGGCCAAUAUGGUGAAACCCUGUCUCUACUAAAAAUACAAAAAAUUAGCCAGGCACGGUGGUGGGCACCUGUAAUCUCAGCUACUGGGGAGGCUGAGGCAGGAGAAUUGCUUGAACCUGGGAGGUGGAGGUUGCAGUGAGCCGAGAUUGUGCCAUUGCACACCAGCCCGGGCGACAGUGUGAGACUCUGUCUCAAAAAAAAAAAAAAAAAGCAUUCAUAAUUACACUAAUCCUAAAAGCUUUAAAGUAGGGGUUCACAAAGAUAAUCAUAUAUACUAAAAAGCAGUAAUAAUGAACAGACUAGUAAGUAUGGAGUGUAUAUGCUACCAAAGAUAUAUUUCUUGGGAGUAUUGUCUACAUGUUCACUGUGUCUUUUGCCCUUCUUGAAAUCUAAGGGUCUCAUUCUUUCAUUCUUCUCUCGUGUCCCUCCCUUCUUCUCUUCUCUCCCCUUUUUUCCUUCGCUCUUUUCUUUACUUCUCUUUCUCUCUUCCUCCUUUCUUCCUUGUUUUCUCCCUCCUUUUCUUUCUUCCUUCUUUCCUUCCUCCCUUCCAGCUCUUAUAUAUUGUCCCAGCUACAUAACAUUUCAUUUUUACUUGUGAAUCAGAGGGUUCAGGGGAUGAAAAAAGAGGGACAGGAGACCCACAGUCUUUUGAUGCCAGCCCUGGUUUUAUAAAUGGAAACUUUAAGAGGAGUCAGAAAAAUCCGUUUUUCUUUCUCCUGCUAUUGAACAGGAGAGCCACAUUUGAAGUGACCUGCAGACCCUAGGGAAGCCUUGCUCAGUAACUAUUUGUUGAUUCAUUGAUUAAACAGCAUGGAGAGAAGGGGCAUCAAGCACGGAGAUCCCCUUAGUAGUGAAAGCUUUGAAACUCCAAGCUGCAGUGUGCAGUAGGAUGGCUUCUCUGUGACCUUCCAACAACUAAUCUCCUUUAAGAACUGAAUCAAAGCAGUUAAGAGAUUCUGUAAGAUGGAUUUUGCCUACAGUUGGGUUUUUGGCAGUUGCAUGUAGAAAGCAAUACAUUCUUCAUGAGGAUUUUUUUUUUUUUUUUUUUUUUUUUUUUUUUUGUCCAGAAAGGAAUGAAGACAAGGUGCCAGCAGAGAUCUCUAGAGAGAGACUCUUAUUUAGCCAUGGUACUAUUCGGGCAGAGACAGCUGCAAGGUGGAUGACUUUCUCACACUUCCCAGCCAACCUUCUUUUUAACCACCCUUGUCUGAUGCUCCAGUCAACAAGCACAUCAGUGCAGUGGGCUUCUCUCUACAAUCUUCUUUCCCAAGGGCAGAGAACAUGCCCUUGGGAGAUAUCAUAUGACUGGAUAUCAUAUGAAUGACAAUGGGUAUUUGUCAUGUUUUUCUAGGGAAAUCAUAGCAAGUAGCAGGCUAGAGAUGAAAUUCCUCAUUUUAAUAGAUAAAUAAGUUGCCCACACAACACAUGAGCUGCAAAACCAGGGCUAUGGCUUGCGAUUUCAGAUUCCCAAUCUAGAACUUUGUUGAGGGCUUCUGCUUUCUAAUAAAUAGAUAACAGAAGAGACAGCUCGUGUCAUAGGAGAAAAAACACACACACCCCCAGUUUAGAAAAUAGUAAAACUAUCUUAAAGGGACUGCUCAAAAGAAUCAUUAUAGGUCUGGUUCAAAUCCUGAAGCUGUAAUUUCAAAAUUCCGCAAUCCUUGGGAAAGAUGCUUAGCCAUUCUGAGCAGUGGUUCCCUUUGUUGUAAAGCUGGGGUUAAAAUAACUAUAAUGUCUAUAUUUUAGGCCUAUUUUGAGGAUUAAAUAAGAUUAUAUAUUUAAAAUGCCUAUUCCAGUGAUUAACACAAAAUAAAUACCAGUAAUAUUAUUGUACUCUUCUUUCCCUCUUCAGGUCAGUGGUAUAUGGUAGAAUUAUGAGAAAAGUCUUAUAAGUAUGCCUCUGGAAUAGUGUAGCUCAGUGGUUUUCAACAUUUUCUUCUGCUGUAACACAUACAGAAAACAUAUGUGAAGAAUCACCACAUCCCUGGCAUAGAGUGAUCAAUAUAUAAUAAUACGAUGGUGGUGAUGAUAACUGUGGUGGUGAUGACAGAGAUGCUGAUGCUGACGGGUGACAUGCACAUACUGCAGAUGAGCACUGGACUCUGAGUAAUUCCAGAGCUUUAGCUUGGAUUGCACUGCUUUUCUACACUAGAGAGGAAAUCAGAAUGUUACUGAACAUCAAUAAUUACAUUAUAAGUGCAACUGCACCCAUUUAAAUUAAAAAGAAAAUCAUCAGCAGGCUCCAGUACUUUAUUACUGGUAACAAAUUACUGGCAACAUACCAGUUGGUUUAGAAGAUGCCAUCUUUCCUGGAGGAAGAUGAUUUUGGAAAAUGCUUUACAUCAUAGCUCUAGAACUAGACCCCAGGGGUUUGAAUUCUGGCUCAUGUAUCUGCGAUGACCUAGGGAAGUAACUGAACUACUCUUCAUCUCUCUUUCCUCAUCUGAAAUUGGAAUAAUAGUUAUACCCACUUCAUCAGAUUGUUUUGAGGAUGAAAUGAAUGAACACAUGUAGAUUACCAAGAAAAUGUCUGGCAUACAGUAAGCAUUCAGUGACUAUUAGACAUUAUUGGAGGUUUUUGUCUCCAAGCUAUUUGAUGGGGCAACAUCCUAUUUUGAAAUUCUCCCUACAAAUUGCCAAUAUUGAAGUUAGUCAAGGUGCCAUUAAUAUAUAAAACUGAUUUUUAGUUUUCACAUAAUAGUAUCUGCUCCUUACUGUUCACUUACCAUGUAACCAGGCAUUAGGCUAUGUGUUUUACCAGUAUCUUAAUUGAUAUAAUUCUCUCAUUACUCUUAUCAGAUAGAUAUUUUUACCCCUAUCUUAUACAUGAGAAAAUUGAGCCCCCAAAAUGAAACUUGCCCAAGUUCACACAGACUAAUAAGUGACAGAGCCAAGCCUCAAAUUCAUAAACUUCCCUACAUAUAUACAUAUUGCUUCAUUAAGUUAGAGAAAAUUUGCAGGGCUUGUGGGAAAGGUGUUUUUGUUUGUUUGUUUGUUUUUUGUUUUUUUGCAAUGAAGGAGAGACCCAAUACAUAACUGCAUUUAUUCUAGGGUAUUCAAAAGUCUCAUAGCAGAAACAUGGAAGGCAAUCACAAUAAAAAGCAAUUUAAUUUUGCUAUUUAAUAAUCACAGAAAUAUCACAGAACUCAAAUUUAAUUCUGUCUUAUGGAGAAGAAGAAAUGGCAGUGGUGGACAAGAAUAAUGGGACAAUGAGGAGAAGAAAGAGGAGGAGGAAGAAGAGAAAGUGGAGAGAAGGAAAGAAAGAGAAAGGCAGAAGUAGGUGGCUCUCAUUUAACAGGUCACCAGUUCUGGAAGUAGAGUGUCUGGGAUCAUCAUUUCCAUUUCAGACAUUAUUUUGUCCAAGGUAACACAGCUAGAAAUAGUGGAAUUGAGAUUUACAUUGUGGUAUUUUACCUUCGAAUCAAGUGAACUCUUCUACUCUAUUUUGCUAUCUUUUGAGACAGAGAUUCAUGUAAAAAUAUAGACACAGAAAGAGGCAUGGAGAGAAGUAUAGGUACAUUUAUGUGAGGACAAACAAUGUUAAAAGCAUUAUUUUACUUUUCCAGAUUUUAACAUUGGUCUGGAGUGGUGGCUUACGCCUGUCAUGCCAGCACUUUGGGAGGCCAAAGUGGGGUGGAUAACCUGAGGUCAGGGGUUCGAGACCAACCUGGCCAAUGUGGUGAAACCUUGUCUCUACUGAAAACACAAAAAUUAGCCAGACCUGGUGGCACAUGCCUAUAAUCCCAGCUACUGGGAGGCUGAGGCAGGAGAAUCGCUUGAACCUGGGAAGCAUAGGUUGCAGUGAGCCAAGAUCACACCACUGCACUCCAGCCUGGGCGAUAGUGUGAGACUCCAUCUCAAAAAAAAAAAAAUUAACUUUGGAGAUUUUCUAAACUCCUGUUGUACUUUUGCAAAUAUAGACAUAAAUUAGAUUAAUCUAUAUUAGAAUACUAGGAGUUUAAUACUAUUUGAUGAUUUUUAUUUUAAAAUAGCUUUUACUUCUCUUAAUUGAUAUUUUAAAGUAUUGUGAACUAAAUAAGCCACAUUCUUCCUAAUUUUACAGAUGAAGAAACUGAGUUAUGUAGUUUCCCUAAGAUCACCUCAACUUACAGCCAAAAUGAGAGUCAUUCUCUGCAUUUUACCCCCACUUCCUGGACCCUUGCCCCAGAAAGAUUUUUCUCUCUACUUUGGUGAUCUCUUCCAAUUAGAAUCAACUUAUAGGAACUUGGGGACAUGUGGAUGGAGGAGAGUCACAUCUUUGUAUAUAAUGAGGGUCUUCCUGGGAAAUGGAAAUAGGUGACCAUUUUUUGUAGGUUUUGCUAUUGCCUUUGAGUCUGGGACACCAUCAUCUGGUCUUUAAGGAAUGAUGUGAGGGUUGUGAUUUACAACAUUAUUUUUUUUCUUAGAAUCCAGGCUGGGGCCUGGAGGGAAUCCUGUGCCUUCUUGUGCUGUAGCUUCCUGGAGUCCACCAGACACUAUGGUGUCUUCCCUAGAGAGUUGCCUGCUGCUUCUGUGAUGUGGCCGACUGGCACUCUGUAGAGCAGACGGAAUUCCCUUCUGAGAGAGCUGACAAUUUACUGGUUCAUCAAUGAAACAAUAUUAAAUUAUGAAGAUGUAAGGAAAAAAUCCUACGCUAACACUGUCGCAGUUUGAAAGUUUUUGGAGUCUACUAAUCUCCAAACCCUGCUCCUGACCCUGAAGCUACAGUGAUGACGAGGAGACAGAGCCCCAGCACUCACAGACCUCAAUGUCUAGUGGAGGUGUUCCGUUAUUACCUUUAAAAAGUUGAAGUCUAUUGGAAACCUUCUUAUAAGAAACCUUCCUAGUCAGAGAAUUCAACUUUCUUCUUUUCUUCAUUCAUGAAAAUGCAGAUCCACUGAGAAAGGGAAUAAGACUUGAAUGAGACCUGCCUCAUCAGUCAUGGGAUCAUAGUGUCACAGAUGGAAAAGCAACUAUCAGCUGAAUUGUACUGAACUACACACUUGGCUAAUUCAUCUUAUUGCUCUACACAUCUAAAGGAAGGCUCAUUCUGUUCUUGGAGUCUAGACAGCAUCAGGAGUUGGGCUCAGUGAACAAAACUUUAAUGUCUAGAGCAUUUAUGAGGGUUUUAAUGAUUGGAAAAUCUAUCCUGAGAAUGUGGUCACCAUAUGUGACAGCCUUGCUUUCUAUCUUGUCUUCAGUUUCUGGGAACUGAUGUAAAGUUCCCAUCAUGAAUGUAAUUAGGAAUUGUGCAUUUAGAUCCUGAAUGUGGCGAGAAUGUGAUUGGGGUCUUGGAGCAGUCAAGUCUGAUCUGGCCUGUGUUCCUUCAGCUAAAAGGCUUCUCUGCAGAAUGUCAAACAAAGAUCGACACAUUGAUUCCAGCUGUUCGUCCUUCAUCAAGACGGAACCUUCCAGCCCAGCCUCCCUGACGGACAGCGUCAACCACCACAGCCCUGGUGGCUCUUCAGACGCCAGUGGGAGCUACAGUUCAACCAUGAAUGGCCAUCAGAACGGACUUGACUCGCCACCUCUCUACCCUUCUGCUCCUAUCCUGGGAGGUAGUGGGCCUGUCAGGAAACUGUAUGAUGACUGCUCCAGCACCAUUGUUGAAGAUCCCCAGACCAAGUGUGAAUACAUGCUCAACUCGAUGCCCAAGAGACUGUGUUUAGUGUGUGGUGACAUCGCUUCUGGGUACCACUAUGGGGUAGCAUCAUGUGAAGCCUGCAAGGCAUUCUUCAAGAGGACAAUUCAAGGCAAUAUAGAAUACAGCUGCCCUGCCACGAAUGAAUGUGAAAUCACAAAGCGCAGACGUAAAUCCUGCCAGGCUUGCCGCUUCAUGAAGUGUUUAAAAGUGGGCAUGCUGAAAGAAGGGGUGCGUCUUGACAGAGUACGUGGAGGUCGGCAGAAGUACAAGCGCAGGAUAGAUGCGGAGAACAGCCCAUACCUGAACCCUCAGCUGGUUCAGCCAGCCAAAAAGCCAUUGCUCUGGUCUGAUCCUGCAGAUAACAAGAUUGUCUCACAUUUGUUGGUGGCUGAACCGGAGAAGAUCUAUGCCAUGCCUGACCCUACUGUCCCCGACAGUGACAUCAAAGCCCUCACUACACUGUGUGACUUGGCCGACCGAGAGUUGGUGGUUAUCAUUGGAUGGGCGAAGCAUAUUCCAGGCUUCUCCACGCUGUCCCUGGCGGACCAGAUGAGCCUUCUGCAGAGUGCUUGGAUGGAAAUUUUGAUCCUUGGUGUCGUAUACCGGUCUCUUUCGUUUGAGGAUGAACUUGUCUAUGCAGACGAUUAUAUAAUGGACGAAGACCAGUCCAAAUUAGCAGGCCUUCUUGAUCUAAAUAAUGCUAUCCUGCAGCUGGUAAAGAAAUACAAGAGCAUGAAGCUGGAAAAAGAAGAAUUUGUCACCCUCAAAGCUAUAGCUCUUGCUAAUUCAGACUCCAUGCACAUAGAAGAUGUUGAAGCCGUUCAGAAGCUUCAGGAUGUCUUACAUGAAGCGCUGCAGGAUUAUGAAGCUGGCCAGCACAUGGAAGACCCUCGUCGAGCUGGCAAGAUGCUGAUGACACUGCCACUCCUGAGGCAGACCUCUACCAAGGCCGUGCAGCAUUUCUACAACAUCAAACUAGAAGGCAAAGUCCCAAUGCACAAACUUUUUUUGGAAAUGUUGGAGGCCAAGGUCUGACUAAAAGCUCCCUGGGCCUUCCCAUCCUUCAUGUUGAAAAAGGGAAAAUAAACCCAAGAGUGAUGUCGAAGAAACUUAGAGUUUAGUUAACAACAUCAAAAAUCAACAGACUGCACUGAUAAUUUAGCAGCAAGACUAUGAAGCAGCUUUCAGAUUCCUCCAUAGGUUCCUGAUGAGUUUCUUUCUACUUUCUCCAUCAUCUUCUUUCCUCUUUCUUCCCACAUUUCUCUUUCUCUUUAUUUUUUCUCCUUUUCUUCUUUCACCUCCCUUAUUUCUUUGCUUCUUUCAUUCCUAGUUCCCAUUCUCCUUUAUUUUCUUCCCGUCUGCCUGCCUUCUUUCUUUUCUUUACCUACUCUCAUUCCUCUCUUUUCUCAUCCUUCCCCUUUUUUCUAAAUUUGAAAUAGCUUUAGUUUAAAAAAAAAUCCUCCCUUCCCCCUUUCCUUUCCCUUUCUUUCCUUUUUCCCUUUCCUUUUCCCUUUCCUUUCCUUUCCUCUUGACCUUCUUUCCAUCUUUCUUUUUCUUCCUUCUGCUGCUGAACUUUUAAAAGAGGUCUCUAACUGAAGAGAGAUGGAAGCCAGCCCUGCCAAAGGAUGGAGAUCCAUAAUAUGGAUGCCAGUGAACUUAUUGUGAACCAUACUGUCCCCAAUGACUAAGGAAUCAAAGAGAGAGAACCAACGUUCCUAAAAGUACAGUGCAACAUAUACAAAUUGACUGAGUGCAGUAUUAGAUUUCAUGGGAGCAGCCUCUAAUUAGACAACUUAAGCAACGUUGCAUCGGCUGCUUCUUAUCAUUGCUUUUCCAUCUAGAUCAGUUACAGCCAUUUGAUUCCUUAAUUGUUUUUUCAAGUCUUCCAGGUAUUUGUUAGUUUAGCUACUAUGUAACUUUUUCAGGGAAUAGUUUAAGCUUUAUUCAUUCAUGCAAUACUAAAGAGAAAUAAGAAUACUGCAAUUUUGUGCUGGCUUUGAACAAUUACGAACAAUAAUGAAGGACAAAUGAAUCCUGAAGGAAGAUUUUUAAAAAUGUUUUGUUUCUUCUUACAAAUGGAGAUUUUUUUGUACCAGCUUUACCACUUUUCAGCCAUUUAUUAAUAUGGGAAUUUAACUUACUCAAGCAAUAGUUGAAGGGAAGGUGCAUAUUAUCACGGAUGCAAUUUAUGUUGUGUGCCAGUCUGGUCCCAAACAUCAAUUUCUUAACAUGAGCUCCAGUUUACCUAAAUGUUCACUGACACAAAGGAUGAGAUUACACCUACAGUGACUCUGAGUAGUCACAUAUAUAAGCACUGCACAUGAGAUAUAGAUCCGUAGAAUUGUCAGGAGUGCACCUCUCUACUUGGGAGGUACAAUUGCCAUAUGAUUUCUAGCUGCCAUGGUGGUUAGGAAUGUGAUACUGCCUGUUUGCAAAGUCACAGACCUUGCCUCAGAAGGAGCUGUGAGCCAGUAUUCAUUUAAGAGGCAAUAAGGCAAAUGCCAGAAUUAAAAAAAAAAAUCAUCAAAGACAGAAAAUGCCUGACCAAAUUCUAAAACCUAAUCCAUAUAAGUUUAUUCAUUUAGGAAUGUUCGUUUAAAUUAAUCUGCAGUUUUUACCAAGAGCUAAGCCAAUAUAUGUGCUUUUCAACCAGUAUUGUCACAGCAUGAAAGUCAAGUCAGGUUCCAGACUGUUAAGAGGUGUAAUCUAAUGAAGAAAUCAAUUAGAUGCCCCGAAAUCUACAGUCGCUGAAUAACCAAUAAACAGUAACCUCCAUCAAAUGCUAUACCAAUGGACCAGUGUUAGUAGCUGCUCCCUGUAUUAUGUGAACAGUCUUAUUCUAUGUACACAGAUGUAAUUAAAAUUGUAAUCCUAACAAACAAAAGAAAUGUAGUUCAGCUUUUCAAUGUUUCAUGUUUGCUGUGCUUUUCUGAAUUUUAUGUUGCAUUCAAAGACUGUUGUCUUGUUCUUGUGGUGUUUGGAUUCUUGUGGUGUGUGCUUUUAGACACAGGGUAGAAUUAGAGACAAUAUUGGAUGUACAAUUCCUCAGGAGACUACAGUAGUAUAUUCUAUUCCUUACCAGUAAUAAGGUUCUUCCUAAUAAUAAUUAAGAGAUUGAAACUCCAAACAAGUAUUCAUUAUGAACAGAUACACAUCAAAAUCAUAAUAAUAUUUUCAAAACAAGGAAUAAUUUCUCUAAUGGUUUAUUAUAGAAUACCAAUGUAUAGCUUAGAAAUAAAACUUUGAAUAUUUCAAGAAUAUAGAUAAGUCUAAUUUUUAAAUGCUGUAUAUAUGGCUUUCACUCAAUCAUCUCUCAGAUGUUGUUAUUAACUCGCUCUGUGUUGUUGCAAAACUUUUUGGUGCAGAUUCGUUUCCAAAACUAUUGCUACUUUGUGUGCUUUAAACAAAAUACCUUGGGUUGAUGAAACAUCAACCCAGUGCUAGGAAUACUGUGUAUCUAUCAUUAGCUAUAUGGGACUAUAUUGUAGAUUGUGGUUUCUCAGUAGAGAAGUGACUGUAGUGUGAUUCUAGAUAAAUCAUCAUUAGCAAUUCAUUCAGAUGGUCAAUAACUUGAAAUUUAUAGCUGUGAUAGGAGUUCAGAAAUUGGCACAUCCCUUUAAAAAUAACAACAGAAAAUACAACUCCUGGGAAAAAAGGUGCUGAUUCUAUAAGAUUAUUUAUAUAUGUAAGUGUUUAAAAAGAUUAUUUUCCAGAAAGUUUGUGCAGGGUUUAAGUUGCUACUAUUCAACUACACUAUAUAUAAAUAAAAUAUAUACAAUAUAUACAUUGUUUUCACUGUAUCACAUUAAAGUACUUGGGCUUCAGAAGUAAGAGCCAACCAACUGAAAACCUGAGAUGGAGAUAUGUUCAAAGAAUGAGAUACAAUUUUUUAGUUUUCAGUUUAAGUAACUCUCAGCAUUACAAAAGAGUAAGUAUCUCACAAAUAGGAAAUAAAACUAAAACGUGGAUUUAAAAAGAACUGCACGGGCUUUAGGGUAAAUGCUCAUCUUAAACCUCACUAGAGGGAAGUCUUCUCAAGUUUCAAGCAAGACCAUUUACUUAAUGUGAAGUUUUGGAAAGUUAUAAAGGUGUAUGUUUUAGCCAUAUGAUUUUAAUUUUAAUUUUGCUUCUUUUAGGUUCGUUCUUAUUUAAAGCAAUAUGAUUGUGUGACUCCUUGUAGUUACACUUGUGUUUCAAUCAGAUCAGAUUGUUGUAUUUAUUCCACUAUUUUGCAUUUAAAUGAUAACAUAAAAGAUAUAAAAAAUUUAAAACUGCUAUUUUUCUUAUAGAAGAGAAAAUGGGUGUUGGUGAUUGUAUUUUAAUUAUUUAAGCGUCUCUGUUUACCUGCCUAGGAAAACAUUUUAUGGCAGUCUUAUGUGCAAAGAUCGUAAAAGGACAAAAAAUUUAAACUGCUUAUAAUAAUCCAGGAGUUGCAUUAUAGCCAGUAGUAAAAAUAAUAAUAAUAAUAAUAAAACCAUGUCUAUAGCUGUAGAUGGGCUUCACAUCUGUAAAGCAAUCAAUUGUAUAUUUUUGUGAUGUGUACCAUACUGUGUGCUCCAGCAAAUGUCCAUUUGUGUAAAUGUAUUUAUUUUAUAUUGUAUAUAUUGUUAAAUGCAAAAAGGAGAUAUGAUUCUGUAACUCCAAUCAGUUCAGAUGUGUAACUCAAAUUAUUAUGCCUUUCAGGAUGAUGGUAGAGCAAUAUUAAACAAGCUUCCACUUUUGACUGCU